AGUAGCAGCCGCCUCCCGCAGCCUCCGCGCGCCGCGGGCUCCUCCUCCCGCCCAAGCGUGGCCAAGUGAGGACUGCUCCGGCCGCAGGUAGCUGAGGCGCGGGAGGCGGCGCGCGCGGGACCCGAGCGGAGCGCCGGGGAGGGGCCGACGGACGCGAGGGCGGACGGACUCCCCAGCCUCCCGUCCCGGACGUUAGCCGAGGUCUGCGCGGGCCAUGUGGGGACCCGGGGUCACUGCUGAGGGCCUGUCGGUGGCUCCGGCGCCGCCGCCUCUGCUGCCGCUGCUGCUACUGCUGGCGCUGGCGCUGGUGGCGCCCUCGCGGGGCGGCGGGGGCUGCGCUGAGCUGGCGUGCGGCGAGCGGGAGCGCUGCUGCGACGCGACCAACGCCACGGCGGUGCGCUGCUGCAAGCUGCCGCUGCACGCCUUCCUGGACAACGUGGGCUGGUUCGUCCGCAAGCUCUCCGGGCUGCUCAUCCUGCUGGUGCUCUUCGCCAUCGGCUAUUUCCUGCAGCGCAUCAUCUGCCCCAGUCCACGCAGGUACCCGCGCGGCCAGGCGCGCCCGGGACAGCGGCCCGGGCCUCCGGGGGGCGCCGGACCGCUGGGGGGCGCGGGGCCGCCCGACGACGACGACGACUCGCCCGCUCUGCUGCGCGACGAGGCGGCAGCCGGCUCUCAGGACUCACUGCUGGACAGUGGCGGCGGCGGCCGGGGCCGGGGAGGCGGCGGGCGCUCGGACCCCUCCUGCGCCUCAGAGCACGAGAUGCGUGUAGUGUCGCCGGUCUUCCUGCAGCUGCCCAGCUACGAGGAGGUCAAGUAUCUGCCCACCUACGAGGAGUCCAUGCGGCUGCAGCAGCUCAGCCCCGGGGAGGUCGUGCUGCCAGUGUCGGUGCUUGGCCGCCCUCGAGGCGGGGUCGCCGCGGAGCCCGACGGCGGCGAGGGCCGCUACCCUCUUAUCUGAGCGCUCGGGGAUCGGCGGCUGGUGCAGGGCUGGGGGCUGCGGGUGGCAAGCAACGGCCGGGGUGCCGCCGCCAACUGCCUCAGACCUUAUCUGGCACCCUGGCCUAACUGCCCGGCACCCCGCGACUGGGUUGGGGUCACUCGUCUCCCUCGCGUUCUCCCGGGAUCUUAUGUUUCUCUGCGUUUCAUUCCGUUCAAAGAAACGUGGGGCACGCGCGGCGGGUGCGGCUGCAGCAGGCGACCCUCCAGCGCACCUUCGAAGGACGUCCCUGCCCUCUGCCUUGCCUCGUAUUGUGGUUCACUAGUAAGUGCCUGCUUCCCUAGUCAAAGAGAACACGUGAGCCCUUUGGUGCGUCGAGAGAAGGGCGGUCUUCUUUAGGGCUGAGGAGAAAGGACCGCAGUUCCACUCCUUUCCCUACCUGCCGCCUGGACAGGUCUCCCAGGGUGGGCAGAGGGCGAGGAGCCGUUGAGGACCAGCCGCGACCAGGGACUGCUGCACGUGGGUGUGGGAGAGCGCCACUUGGUUAUGAUGAAAUCGCUGCCAUGCGGCAGACCCCCCAAAAUCCCUCAGUGUCUUCCUGAUCUAGCAAAUAGUCACAGCUGGUGUUUCACAAUUAGGUGGAGUGCGGGGAGUGGGCUAGGGGGGACACCUGUGAUACAAGGUUAGCUGCUGUACCUACUCAGGGAACAGCAACCAUGUAUAUCCAUUCGGCUGGACUUUUGAUUGUUCAAUAACUGAGGAGGUAUUUAUAUUUAUUUGUCUUUUAUUCUAAUAUUUUUACCAUGCAUUGAACGCAACAGGAGGGUAUUUCAGCAAAUUCACGACAAGGUAAUCGUCUUAUCACUUUUUGUAGGCCAUUAAUGGUCAGGAAAUUGCCCAUACUCUGUCAUUAUUGUUUAAUAAAUCAUUAAAUUAUUUCAUUAAAAAAGAAAAACAGGUAUGGUCAAACGAGGAAGCAUAUGUGACAUAAAAAACAUGAAGGAUAUCUUAUUUUCACUAUUUGAGAAGAAUAUAUUUUAUUUUUAGUACUGUGGCAUAAUAUAUAACUUUUUAUAAUAAUAACUGUAUGCAUUAUGUAGUAUAGCUUUUAAUUGUAUCAUUCAUCACAGUUAUAUGUAAAAAUAAUUGACAUGUAUAUGCCAUACCAUGAAGCAUAUGAUGUUGUGCACUUUCUCCUCCAUUUUUCAUUUGGAAUACAUUCCACAACAUGAUCCAAAACAUAAGAACUUACGACUUGUAACUCGUUUAAAGCCAUUAAUUGUGCAGUAAUGUGCUACAGGAUUCAAUCAGCUUCUCUUAAGAAACAAGUGUCAUUGUAUCAGUUUCCUGUUCUGUGACACGCCCUUUAAAAGUAAAAGAUAAUAUAACAUAUUUUAAUACAUUGUGUGUAAUGUACAUAUGCAUAUUGUCUAUGUACUAUAUACACAUUGUUUAUAAUAUUGUUAUUACAGUUUGUCAUUCACCUGAAAGGAGAAGGAAAAGUACGAAAGGUUUCUCUGCUUGGGAAAAGGUGAAUGUUGUUAUAUCAAGAACGAUUACACACAUGGAUCUCAUACAUGUUUUUAGAACAUUGUUCUUCUGAUUGAAGAAGUCUGAUGCUCCUGAAAAAUCUUAAAAUAUCUGACUUGUAUUGAAGAAAAUUAUUUAAUUAAAUUUUUAAAGGCUGGUUGAAAAAGUCUGACAGUUCUGAGAAUUUUUUAAAUGUCUGAAUUGUAAUAAAAAAAUGGUUUACUUUAAACUUCUAAAAACUAAUGACCUUGUGACUAAAGAAAAAUCAUUUGAAGUGUAUUAAAAAAUAGCAAAACAUUAAAAUCUUUUCUCUGUGCAAAUUUUA